ACAGCUCCCGUCCCGUUACCGCCUCCUGGCCGGCCUCGCGCCUUUCACCGGCACCUUGCGUCGGUCGCGCCGCGGGGCCUGCUCCUGCCGCGCGCACCCCCGGGGCUUCGGCUCCGGCACGGGUCGCGCCCAGCUUUCCUGCACCUGAGGCCGCCGGCCAGCCGCCGCCAUGGGUGCCUACCUCUCCCAGCCCAACACGGUGAAGUGCUCCGGGGACGGGGUCGGCGCCCCGCGCCUGCCGCUGCCCUACGGCUUCUCCGCCAUGCAAGGCUGGCGCGUCUCCAUGGAGGAUGCUCACAACUGUAUUCCUGAGCUGGACAGUGAGACAGCCAUGUUUUCUGUCUACGAUGGACAUGGAGGGGAGGAAGUUGCCUUGUACUGUGCCAAAUAUCUUCCUGAUAUCAUCAAAGAUCAGAAGGCCUACAAGGAAGGCAAGCUACAGAAGGCUUUAGAAGAUGCCUUCUUGGCUAUUGACGCCAAAUUGACCACUGAAGAAGUCAUUAAAGAGCUGGCACAGAUUGCAGGGCGACCCACUGAGGAUGAAGAUGAAAAAGAAAAAGUAGCUGAUGAAGAUGAUGUGGACAAUGAGGAGGCUGCACUGCUGCAUGAAGAGGCUACCAUGACUAUUGAAGAGCUGCUGACACGCUACGGGCAGAACUGUCACAAGGGCCCUCCCCACAGCAAAUCUGGAGGUGGGACAGGCGAGGAACCAGGGUCCCAGGGCCUCAAUGGGGAGGCAGGACCUGAGGACUCAACUAGGGAAACUCCUUCACAAGAAAAUGGCCCCACAGCCAAGGCCUACACAGGCUUUUCCUCCAACUCGGAACGUGGGACUGAGGCAGGCCAAGUUGGUGAGCCUGGCAUUCCCACUGGUGAGGCUGGGCCUUCCUGCUCUUCAGCCUCUGACAAGCUGCCUCGAGUUGCUAAGUCCAAGUUCUUUGAGGACAGUGAGGAUGAGUCAGAUGAGGCGGAGGAAGAAGAGGAAGACAGUGAGGAAUGCAGCGAGGAAGAGGAUGGCUACAGCAGUGAGGAGGCAGAGAAUGAGGAAGAUGAGGAUGACACCGAGGAGGCUGAAGAGGACGAUGAAGAAGAAGAAGAAGAGAUGAUGGUGCCAGGGAUGGAAGGCAAAGAGGAGCCUGGCUCUGACAGUGGUACAACAGCGGUGGUGGCCCUGAUACGAGGGAAGCAGUUGAUUGUAGCCAACGCAGGAGACUCUCGCUGUGUGGUAUCUGAGGCUGGCAAAGCUUUAGACAUGUCCUAUGAUCACAAACCAGAGGAUGAAGUAGAACUAGCACGCAUCAAGAAUGCUGGUGGCAAGGUCACCAUGGAUGGGCGAGUCAACGGGGGCCUCAACCUCUCCAGAGCCAUUGGGGACCACUUCUAUAAGAGAAACAAGAACCUGCCACCUGAGGAACAGAUGAUUUCAGCCCUUCCUGACAUCAAGGUGCUGACUCUCACUGACGACCAUGAAUUCAUGGUCAUUGCCUGUGAUGGCAUCUGGAAUGUGAUGAGCAGCCAGGAAGUUGUAGAUUUCAUUCAAUCAAAGAUCAGCCAGCGUGAUGAAAAUGGGGAGCUUCGGUUAUUGUCAUCCAUUGUGGAAGAGCUGCUGGAUCAGUGCCUGGCACCAGACACUUCUGGGGAUGGUACAGGGUGUGACAACAUGACCUGCAUCAUCAUUUGCUUCAAGCCCCGAAACACAGCAGAGCUCCAGCCAGAGAGUGGCAAGCGAAAACUAGAGGAGGUGCUCUCUACUGAGGGGGCUGAAGAAAAUGGCAACAGCGACAAGAAGAAGAAGGCCAAGCGAGACUAGCAGUCAUCCAGACCCCUGCCCACCUAGACUGUUUUCUGAGCCCUCCGGACCUGAGACUGAGUUUUGUCUUUUUCCUUUAGCCUUAGCAGUGGGUAUGAGGUGUGCAGGGGGAGCUGGGUGGCUUCACUCCGCCCAUUCCAAAGAGGGCUCUCCCUCCACACUGCAGCCGGGAGCCUCUGCUGUCCUUCCCAGCCGCCUCUGCUCCUCGGGCUCAUCACCGGUUCUGUGCCUGUGCUCUGUUGUGUUGGAGGGAAGGACUGGCGGUUCUGGUUUUUACUCUGUGAACUUUAUUUAAGGACAUUCUUUUUUAUUGGCGGCUCCAUGGCCCUCGGCCGCUUGCACCCGCUCUCUGUUGUACACUUUCAAUCAACACUUUUUCAGACUAAAGGCCAAAACCUAA